CUUUCGGUGCUCGACUCGCCCGUGCUGCUGCCGCCGCCGAAGGAGGGGCAAAGCUCAAGAUGGCGGACAAAACGCCAGGCGGAUCUCAGAAGGCCAGUUCAAAGACGAGAUCAUCAGAUGUUCAUUCAUCUGGAUCUUCAGAUGCACAUAUGGAUGCAUCUGGACCCUCAGAUAGUGAUAUGCCAAGUCGGACACGACCUAAGAGCCCAAGAAAACAUAAUUAUAGGAAUGAAAGUGCCCGUGAAAGCCUUUGUGAUUCUCCUCAUCAGAAUCUCUCAAGACCUCUUCUGGAAAACAAACUUAAAGCAUUCAGUAUUGGAAAAAUGAGUACAGCUAAGCGAACUUUAAGUAAAAAGGAACAGGAAGAAUUAAAGAAAAAGGAGGAUGAAAAGGCAGCUGCUGAGAUUUAUGAGGAGUUUCUUGCUGCUUUUGAAGGAAGUGAUGGUAAUAAAGUGAAAACAUUUGUGCGAGGGGGUGUUGUUAAUGCAGCUAAAGAAGAACAUGAAACAGAUGAAAAAAGAGGUAAAAUCUAUAAGCCAUCUUCAAGAUUUGCAGAUCAAAAAAAUCCUCCAAAUCAGUCUUCCAAUGAAAGACCACCAUCUCUUCUUGUGAUAGAAACCAAAAAACCUCCACUUAAAAAAGGAGAGAAAGAAAAGAAAAAAAGCAAUUUGGAACUCUUCAAAGAAGAAUUAAAGCAAAUUCAAGAGGAACGUGAUGAGAGACAUAAAACAAAAGGCAGAUUAAGUCGAUUUGAACCUCCUCAGUCAGAUUCUGAUGGUCAGCGUCGUUCUAUGGACGCGCCUUCAAGAAGAAAUAGAUCAUCUGGUGUUCUUGAUGAUUACGCACCUGGCUCACAUGAUGUAGGAGAUCCAAGCACUACUAAUUUAUACCUUGGAAACAUUAAUCCACAGAUGAAUGAAGAAAUGCUGUGCCAAGAAUUUGGAAGAUUUGGACCGUUAGCCAGUGUGAAAAUCAUGUGGCCUAGAACUGAUGAAGAAAGAGCCAGAGAGAGAAAUUGCGGCUUUGUGGCCUUUAUGAAUAGAAGAGAUGCUGAAAGAGCUUUAAAAAAUUUGAAUGGAAAAAUGAUUAUGUCUUUUGAAAUGAAGUUAGGUUGGGGUAAAGCUGUACCUAUUCCUCCACAUCCAAUAUACAUUCCGCCUUCUAUGAUGGAACAUACGCUUCCCCCACCUCCAUCCGGACUGCCUUUUAAUGCGCAGCCUAGAGAGCGGUUAAAAAACCCUAAUGCUCCUAUGUUACCGCCACCUAAAAACAAAGAGGAUUUUGAGAAGACUCUGUCGCAAGCCAUAGUCAAAGUGGUUAUCCCAACAGAAAGAAGAAAUUCCUAUUAUUGUCAUGAACACUGGACAUACUAGAAACUUUCUUUUCAUGGUAACAAAGGAAUUUGCUCGCCCUGAUACAUCGAAUGAUAGAGUUUGUUGUACGUGAAGGGCCAAUGUUUGAAGCUAUGAUUAUGAACAGAGAAAUCAACAAUCCUAUGUUCAGGUUCUUAUUUGAAAACCAGACACCAGCCCAUGUUUACUAUAGGUGGAAGCUUUAUUCUAUUCUGCAGGGAGAUUCUCCAACUAAAUGGCGGACGGAAGAUUUUCGUAUGUUCAAAAAUGGAUCUUUUUGGAGGCCACCACCAUUAAAUCCGUACUUGCAUGGAAUGUCAGAAGAGCAAGAAACAGAAGCUUUUGUAGAGGAACCUAGUAAAAAGGGAGCACUUAAGGAAGAACAGAGGGAUAAAUUGGAAGAAAUCUUGCGGGGAUUAACUCCAAGGAAAAAUGAUAUUGGAGAUGCAAUGGUUUUCUGUCUUAAUAAUGCUGAAGCUGCUGAAGAAAUAGUGGAUUGCAUUACUGAGUCGUUGUCCAUCUUAAAGACACCCCUUCCUAAAAAGAUUGCCAGAUUAUAUUUGGUUUCUGAUGUUUUGUACAACUCUUCAGCCAAAGUUGCUAAUGCUUCAUAUUAUAGAAAAUUUUUUGAAACAAAGUUAUGUCAGAUAUUUUCAGACCUCAAUGCCACCUAUCGUACAAUUCAAGGCCAUUUACAAUCUGAAAACUUUAAGCAACGGGUAAUGACUUGCUUCAGAGCAUGGGAAGAUUGGGCAAUUUAUCCAGAACCAUUUUUGAUCAAACUACAAAAUAUUUUCUUAGGACUUGUAAAUAUUAUUGAAGAAAAGGAAACAGAGGAUGUUCCAGAUGACCUUGAUGGUGCCCCCAUCGAGGAAGAGCUUGAUGGUGCACCUCUGGAAGAUGUAGAUGGAAUUCCUAUUGAUGCUACUCCCAUCGAUGAUCUUGAUGGAGUCCCUAUAAAAAGUCUUGAUGAUGAUCUUGAUGGAGUGCCUUUGGAUGCAACUGAAGACUCAAAAAAGAAUGAGCCUAUAUUUAAAGUUGCCCCAUCAAAAUGGGAAGCUGUGGAUGAAUCUGAAUUGGAAGCACAGGCUGUUACAACUUCUAAAUGGGAAUUAUUUGACCAGCAUGAAGAAUCAGAAGAAGAAGAAAAUCAAAAUCAAGAAGAAGAAAGUGAAGAUGAAGAAGAUACUCAAAGUUCCAAAUCUGAAGAACAUCAUUUGUACUCUAAUCCAAUCAAAGAAGAAAUGACUGAGUCUAAGUUCUCUAAGUACUCUGAAAUGAGUGAGGAAAAACGAGCCAAACUUCGUGAAAUUGAGCUCAAAGUUAUGAAGUUUCAGGAUGAAUUGGAAUCUGGGAAAAGACCUAAAAAACCAGGCCAGAGUUUUCAGGAGCAAGUAGAACACUACAGAGAUAAACUUCUUCAACGAGAGAAAGAGAAAGAGUUAGAAAGAGAACGAGAAAGAGACAAGAAAGAUAAAGAAAAAUUGGAAUCUCGCUCCAAAGACAAGAAGGAAAAAGAUGAGUGUACUCCGACAAGGAAGGAAAGGAAGAGGCGACACAGUACAUCCCCCAGCCCAUCUCGCAGUAGCAGUGGUAGACGAGUGAAAUCCCCAUCACCAAAAUCGGAGCGAUCAGAGCGUUCAGAAAGAUCUCAUAAAGAGAGCUCACGGUCCAGGUCAUCUCACAAAGAUUCUCCUAGAGAUGUUAGCAAAAAAGCCAAAAGAUCACCAUCUGGUUCAAGGACACCUAAAAGGUCUAGGCGAUCACGGUCUAGAUCUCCUAAAAAAUCAGGAAAGAAGUCCAGAUCCCAGUCCAGAUCUCCACACAGGUCUCAUAAAAAGUCAAAGAAAAACAAACACUGACGUAAAUUUUUAAGAUGCUGUCACUUAUUGGAAAUGCGAUUUGUUUUGUGCCUGAACGGUCUGUUUUUUAAAAAAACAAAAAAUCAAAUGAAAGAGCAUUCCUGGGGUUUUUUGUUUGUUUGUGUAUGCAUGUGUAAACUCAUGAGCAACUGCAUCUGUAGAUCUGUCAUUGUUUUAUAUUGUGUAAAUUACUUUCAUUGUGGCUAUUUCUCAAGAUGAAAUUUUUAUUGUUCUAAUGGAUUUCAUCAGAAAUGUGUAUAAUGGAUCUGCUGACAGUAGUAGUAUUUUGUUUUAGGAUGUUGUGACUUAGCAAAAAUAAUACAGAUGUCUUCCCCCCUUUUGUAGCUUUGACAAUUUGAAUUAGAUUUCAAAUAAAAUCUGAACAGAAAACUAUAAUGUUGUUUUUUUGCCCCACCGGUGAUAUUAAGUCCCUUAAAGUCCUACUGAGUUUCACACUACUGUUGUGCUUCUUAUACCUGAUGCACUUUAUAAGCCCCAGUGUUCAAGUAGCUUAAGUUUUAUAUUUACUAAGAUGACUAUCCAAAUUAAGGGACCUGAGACUCCUAUUUGGUGGUUUGCUAACCAUUUGCUUUUGAUAAGUUUCUCUUGGGUAAUACUAAUACCCAGAUAUCAAAGACUAGGUAGAUAUGGCAUGGCGUUUUGUUAGUGGAAUGCCUGGCUAAAACAUUUUUUUCACAGAAGCAAUAUGAUUUCCAUACAUCCAACCCAUGUUCUGAGCAACUACUUACUUUUAGGGGGAAAUUAAAUAUCUUUUCAUUUCCUCUUCUAUUAUGAAAGAAGUUUAUUUGUAAAACAAAUUUUCUAACAAGGUUUGGCCAUAGAAUUCUCUUGUAUGAUCGUUGACCUUUUAUAAUCUUCUGUAGGCUAUCUUUCAAACACUGGCAUCAGAAUAUUUUUUAUAAGUUUGUGUUUAAACAGCUUAGUUGGUCCCCCCCCACUCCCAAGAGACUUGGGUUUAGUUAUAGCUUUAAGUAAAAUUUAAAAAUAAAAUGUUUUUCAGGAAACUUCGUAUCUAAUGGUUUGUAAAUUCAAGGUGCAAAAAGUUGAUUUAAACCAUUUGCAGAGUUGAACUCUAUUAUGAAAAUAAAUUUGCUACGGUAUGAGGAAGAAAUAAAACUUGUGUAAUGUUGGUCAUAAUACUGCUAUAAAUAUAAUAAAGGGUUAUGUAGAAUUGAACUGACACUAUUAUUUGUGAAUCUUGAUUUCAGUUUUUUAUGUAGGCACUUCAUACACUGGUUUGAUGGGUUUUUUUUUUCCUCCCUAAAAGAGAAAGUAGAAAACUAUUCUAACAAUGGAUUAUUUUGAUUUAGCUUGCUUUUUAAAAAAAUCUUUUCAACUUGUUUUACUUAAUCUUGCCUAGUCACAAAAUAAGAUGUGCACCCAUGGUUUGGAGAGUUCCUAUAUUAGCUGAGCAGUGAGAUACACUAUUUCCAAACGGUGCACACCUACAGUAGCUUUGGAAAUGAGCCAAUCACUGUUUUACUUAAUGGUUCUUAUCAGCAUGCAAAUAUUGCUUGAAAGUUAUUUCCUUAUUCACUGUUUUGUUAGUCCAUUUUGUUAGGAAACAUUAAUUCCUAAAAAUUUGUUCAGAAUAAUUAAAAGUGAACAUUUGGUGCUGAUACUCAAAAACCUACAAAUGUAGCCAUUUAAAAAGUAACAUGUUUUUCUCCCCUGCUCAUUGCCUGGGAGAAUGGAAUUUUAUAUAACUACCUUUCUUUGCAAAAAUAACGGUCGUGUCGAGUUGGUGGUGAUUUUGGCAUUCCAUCUUGCACUGGUUUCUAGUAUAGGCUUAGAAAUAAUUGGUCAGGUAAUAAUCUUUCCAGUCAAGUUGCAAGGGAUGCUUAUUUCUCUUCAAAAAAAGACAUCCUGCGGGAUUGAGUAGAAAAUUUUAGGUCAGUUUUGGGUGCUUAUUUGUAAUAUUUUUCCUACUACAUUGGAGUUUAGCAGUUCUUUUUUUCUGGAUCCAGAUACAAGUGUCAUGGUUUAUCUUACAGUGGGUGAAACUGACUUUCUUUUGGUUGGGUGGGUGAGGAUUUCUUAGGCCUGAUAGAAUAUAUAUUCUGUGAAGUUUGUUAAUGUACAUAUUAGAUUGUAUUGGAUUUUUUUUUCUUGAAUUGCAAAUGGUAUUAUUAGAUAGGUUAUUUCCAGUUUUACUUCAUGACAAAUUACCUAGAGUAAACCUACUUAAUACUCCCAUGGAUUCUAUGAAAGUUUAAUGGGAUCAGAAAUUGGUGACUUAUAAGGGGGAAGAUAUUCUACCAUAUUUUUAUAAUAGCUUAUUAUUCAUGUUUCUUGUCUGAAGGACACUCAAGUUACAGAGCAAAAUUUCUAUAGGUUGACUAGAAUGUUCAUAAGCAUGGUCUUCCAGUUGCAGGAAAGAUCAUGUUCUAUCUGUGGACACUUACUGUCCUCUACCACAGCUACGUGCCAGAGUUGUUUUCCACAGUUCUUAUAAAGGGCAUGACUUAGGCUCUUUACCCUCCAACUUAAUGUUUAUACACAGGGAUUGUUUACUAGGUUAAUGACAUUUAACUCCCCUCUCUUCUGUAGGUGAGAGAAAAUAAGUAAGUCUUGAUCUGUUUCUUACCAAAGAGAGACAGACCUAUGAUGGAAAAUGAUCACGUCUCUGAAUUUUUUCUUUAACGUUAUAGUUCCUUAUUACAGAUAGUAAGCAUAUGGGAAUUUCUGAGCUAUAACAUGUUGAGAAGUUAGAAAUUAAAACUAACACAACAAAAGGCGCUGAAUCAAAAGAUCUUUGCUUUUAUUUGGCUCAGAAUGUUUUUGGCUUUUCUGCUAAAGAUGGCAGAAAUUACUCUACACAGACCUGAUUUUUCUUUAUUGCAGACCAUUCUUGUGGGCUUACCCUGAGACUUUUAUCCCAAUUAGUGAAUCUUGGAGGGAAUACUUGCUUAUUUAUGACUUAGGUAUUUCCCCCCAAACUUUAAUAUUCUUGAGCACUUGAAAAUACUUUUGAGAAAUUUUAACUGUGAUUAAAUUUAGGUUUAUUAGAAAUAUUCUGUACACAUUUGCCUCCAUGGUGGCGUAAGUUCUGAAAAAUUAUAUGACCGUGACAAUAGUUUAUCAUCAUCAUUAUUGUUAUUCAAAAUAAGGGUAAAUAAAUCUCUGUAUUGCCAAAGUGACUUAAACUGUUCUGAUGACCACACAGUGUGAUUUCUUUAGCAGAGAAAGUUGGUUUUAAAAAUAAAUAGUACCACUUUUCUAAGACUGUACAGUUUACAAAUAAGGUUUUUUUCUUUGUUGUUUUCCUCUUCUAUUAAGUUUUAGUGAAAAGCCUAAUUACAGAAAAUUGUGCAGAUACUAGUGAAGAUACUAGUAUAAGUUUAAAGGAACACGUGACUGUAAAAUCUCACAUUUACAAAGUGCUUGAUCUCUUCAUAUUUCACACGCAUGUUUUAGAAUAGAUUUUAGGGAGUGUUUAAUUCAUUAUCCUUUUGACUUAAAAUUUUUGUUACCAACUUCCUAGGACUUAGAUAAUAUAUAAAUAAGUACAAAUCCCAGGGGAAGUGUUGUGAUGCUAGACUAAAAGGUGGGAAUGUGCUGCUGUUCCGUGAGCCUUGUUCCAUUGUUGAAAAUUUGAUGCCUCAGUGUUUAUUCAGUACCACCUCAUGGAGCUUCAAUGUAAAUGGAUUAUAUGUAUAAUUGGUAAUUUGUAUAGUUUUGUAGAUUGUAGAUUAAAUGCACUCAUCAUGUCACAUGUAAUUGUGCUUGGAGUAUUUGUGUUUUAUUCUUUUACUUCAACGGGUUCUUGUCUGUUACAUCUCUGGUGAUUUGAAAUAUCAGGAAAGACAGUUUGUCAGAAAUGAGAAUAAUAUAGUUGAAAUCAGUUGGGCUAAAAUAUUCUACAGCAAGACAAUUUCUUUUGGGUGAACUGAUUCUAUAAUUUACUUACUUUUAAUGUAAGGAUUAGAUUUAUUGUUGAGCUGCUUUCCAGAUCAGACUGUCACUUUAUAGUUUUUCUACAUAAAGAUUAUAUAGUUGCAAACAAAGGUUGUGAAAUUUCCCUUUUGUUGUUUUUGACUUUUAAUUAAUAAAAGUACAUUGUUUUCAUAGCAAACUUAGACUGUCCAUGUAAUUUUCUCCAUAUUGUUUUUCCGAUGCAAGCCCAGUUAAUAAUUAGUUUUUUAGCAGCUUUCUCUCAAGUGAAAUAAGUGAUGUGACAUGUUUAUCAGUUAUGGCUAAAAUGUUACACUUUACAUGUUUAAACUAUAAUCAUAUGUUUUCAUGCUAGAUGGU